AGUCAACGGGAAUGCGGUAACUGUUGGUAACAGAACAACGAGCUGUGCACCAAGCCAAGUCUCUCUUCGGUGCCACCGGCGGGCGAGGCCGGAUUAAUCACCGCUGCUUCGGCCGCCCAUGUGUCCUGAUGUCCUGGGACCCGAACCCCGUGCCCCGUACCUUGCGAUGCUGGCGCCUACGGAGGGCAUCCGAAACUGCCCUACAGAGCAGUCGCCGGGCAGUUGAAGAUCAGCUAAAGAUAUGUGGCCACAGGAGGGAUGCUGAUGUCUUUGAGCUGUUCCUUUCUAAAAAGGAACUGACAGAGGUCAUUGAUCUUUCUAGGUUUAAAAAAUUAAAAUACUUAUGGCUUCAUCAUAACAAGCUCCAUGGAAUAACAUUUCUAACUAGAAACUAUUGUCUGACAGAACUAUAUCUAAACAACAAUGCAAUAUUUGAGAUAGAAGGUCUGCAUUAUUUGCCUUCAUUGCAUAUACUCCUGCUACACCACAAUGAGCUAACCAACAUUGAUGCAACAGUGAAGGAAUUAAAGGGAAUGCUAAAUCUGAAGAUCCUAAGUCUAUACCAAAAUCCUUUGUGCCAAUAUAACCUGUAUCGUUUAUAUAUCAUCUACCACCUUCCAGGAGUGGAGCUGCUUGACCGAAAUCAAGUUACAGAAAAAGAAAGAAGAUCAAUGAUUACCAUUUUUAACCAUAAAAAGGCUCAUAUCGUUCAAUCAAUAGCAUUCGGAGGAAAAGUGGAUGCUUCAUGGGAUCCUAAAUCACCAUUUAAGCAAAAACCAGCCCAGAGAGUACCUUCAGUGUGCUUUAUGAUUACAAGGUGGCUGGUGUACCCCCAAGCCUCACAUCUCCAUUCCACGAAGGAAGAGAGGGUGGAUAAGAAAAGGUGCAAAGAUUUUGCAUUUGCAAAUAAUGUAGACAAAACUGUGCUUGAUGACCCAGAAGAUGCUGUUUUUGUGAGGUCCAUGAAGAGAUCAGUGAUGACUUUGACCUCUAUGAACUGGGACACAGUUCCAACACGAGAGGAAAGGUACCUUGAAGAGGAAGGCACAGAAACAGCUCAAAUGCUCACAGUUACACUGAGAUAAGCCCUGGUAUUUCUAGAUAUCUUAGUGGUUUUCAGUUGUAUAUUAAACUUCCCUGUGACUUAGCAUAUUACAUACUUAC